AGACCCGGAAGCGGACGGCGUGGAGUGACUAUCCCACCGCCGCGGGAUUGACUUCUAAAGACUCUUGGUAUGUGAGGAAGAAACCUGGAAGAGGAAGAGGAAAGCAAAGGAGUCAGGGAUGGCUCUUCCUCAGGGUCUAUUGACAUUCAGGGAUGUGGCCAUAGAAUUCUCUCAGGAGGAGUGGAAAUGCCUGGACCCUGCUCAGAGGACUCUAUACAGGGACGUGAUGCUGGAGAAUUAUAGGAACCUGGUCUCCCUGGAUAUCUCUUCCAAAUGCAUGAUGAAGGAGUUCUCGUCAACAGCACAAGGCAAUAGAGAAGUGUUCCAUGCAGGGACAUCUCAAAGACAUGAAAGUCAUCACAAUGGAGAUUUUUGUUUCCAGGAUAUUGAUAAAGAUAUUCAUGACAUUGAGUUUCAGUGGCAAGAAGAUGAAAGAAAUGGCCAUGAAGCACUCAUGACAAAAAUCAAAAAGUUGACAGGUAGUACAGAGCGAUAUGAUCAAAAUUAUGCUGGAAACAAGCCUGUUAAAUAUCAGCUUGGAUUCAGCUUUCAUUCGCAUCUGCCUGAACUGCACAUAUUUCACACUGAAGAGAAAAUUGAUAAUCAAGUUGUGAAGUCUAUCCACGAUGCUUCCUUGGUUUCAACAGCCCAAAGAAUUUCUUGUAGGCCUGAAACCCAUAUUUCUAAUGACUAUGGGAAUAAUUUCCUGAAUUCUUCAUUAUUCACACAAAAACAGGAAGUACAUAUGAGGGAAAAAUCUUUCCAAUGCAAUGACAGUGGCAAAGCCUAUAAUUGUAGCUCACUCUUAAGGAAACAUCAGUUAAUCCAUUUAGGAGAGAAACAAUAUAAAUGCGAUAUAUGUGGCAAGGUCUUUAAUUCGAAGCGAUACGUUGCACGCCAUCGUAGAUGUCACACUGGUGAGAAACCUUACAAGUGUAAUGAGUGUGGCAAGACCUUCAGUCAGACAUAUUACCUAACAUGCCAUCGUAGACUUCAUACUGGAGAGAAACCUUACAAAUGUGAAGAAUGUGACAAAGCUUUCCAUUUCAAAUCAAAGCUUCAAAUACAUAGGAGAAUUCAUACUGGAGAGAAACCGUACAAGUGUAAUGAGUGUGGCAAGACCUUUAGUCAGAAGUCGUACCUUACAUGCCAUCGUAGGCUUCAUACUGGAGAGAAACCUUACAAGUGUAAUGAGUGUGGCAAGACCUUUAGUCGGAAGUCACAUUUUACAUGCCAUCAUAGAGUUCAUACUGGAGAGAAACCUUACAAGUGUAAUGAGUGUAGCAAGACCUUUAGUCACAAGUCAUCUCUUACAUACCAUCGUAGACUUCAUACUGAAGAGAAACCUUACAAGUGUAAUGAGUGUGGCAAGACCUUCAAUCAGCAGUUAACCCUUAACAUUUGUAGACUUCAUAGUGGAGAGAAACCUUACAAAUGUGAAGAAUGUGACAAAGCCUACAGUUUCAAAUCAAACCUUGAAAUACAUCAGAAAAUUCAUACUGAAGAGAAUCCUUACAAGUGUAAUGAGUGUGGCAAGACCUUCAGCCGGACGUCAUCCCUUACAUACCAUCAUAGACUUCAUACUGGACAGAAACCUUACAAAUGUGAAGAUUGUGAUGAAGCUUUCAGUUUCAAAUCAAACCUUGAAAGACAUAGGAGAAUUUAUACUGGAGAGAAACUACACGUGUAAUGAGUGUGGUAAGACCUUCAAUCAGGAGUUAACCCUUACAUGCCAUCGUAGGCUUCAUAGUGGAGAGAAACCUUACAAAUAUGAAGAACUUGACAAAGCUUACAAUUUCAAAUCAAACCUUGAAAUACAUCAGAAAAUUCGUACUGAAGAGAAUCUUACAAGUGUAAUGAGUGUGGCAAGACCUUGAGUCAUACGUCAUCUUUUGUGUACCAUCAUAAACUUCAUAGUGGAGAGACCUUACAAAUGUGAAGAAUGUGAAGAAGCUUUCUGUUUCAAAUCCAACCUUGAAAGACAUAGGAGAAUUCACACUGGUGAGAAACCUUACAGGUGUAAUGAGUGUGGCAAGACCUUCAGCCAGACCUCAUCCCUUACAUGCCAUUGUAGACUUCGUACUGGAGAGAAACCUUACAAAUGUGAAGAAUUUGAGUUUUCCAUUUCAAAUCAAACCUUGAAAGACAAAGGAGAAUUCAUACUGGAGAGAAACCAUACAAGUGUAAUGAGUGUGGCAAGACCUUUAGUCAGAACUCAUACCUUACACGCCAUCGUAGACUUCAUACUGGAGGAUACCUUACAAAUGUAAUGAGUGUGGCAAGACCUUUAGUCAGAACUCAUACCUUACAUGCCAUCAUAGACUUCAUACUGGAGAGAUACCUUAAAAGUGUAGUGAGUGUGGCAAGACCUUUAGUCUGAAGUCAUACCUUACGCACCAUCGUAGACUUCAUACUGGAGAGGUACCUUACAAGGAUAAUGAGUGUAGAAAAACCUUUCAUGGGCAGUCAGCAUUUUACAAAUGUAAUGAUUGUCACCAAGUCUUGAGUAAUGCUACAACUAUUGCAAAUCAUUGGAGAAUCCAUAAUGAAGAGAGAUCCUACAAGUGUGAUAAAUGCAGAAUAAAUGCAGAAAAUUUUUCAGACAUCCUUCAUACCUUUGCAGUUCAUGGGUGAAGUCGUAUUAGAAACCUUACAAAUGUGAAGAAUGUGAUGAAGCUUUCAGAUUCAAAUCAAACCUUGAUAGUCAUAGAAUUCAUACUAGAGAGAAACCUUAGCAGUGUAAUGAACGUGGCAAGGUUUUAAAUCAAAAAGCAAAGCUUGCACAUCAUCAUAGAAUUCAUACUGGAGAUAAACGUUACAAAUGUGAAGCAUGUGACAAAGUUUACAGUCGCAAAUCAAGCCUCCAAAGACAGGAGAAUUCAUACUGGAGAGAAAGCUUACAUAUGUGAAGAAUGUCACCAAGUUUUCAGUCACACUCAAACCUUGAAAGACACAGGAGAAUUCCUACUGGAGAGAUAGCAUAAAAAUGUAAGAGUUUGUGACAAGGCUUUCAGGCAUAAUUCGCACCUGGCACAACAUCCUAGAAUUCACAUUGGAGAGAAAGCUUACAAGUAUAAUGAAUGUGACAGGUCUUUAGUGGGCAGUCAACACUUGUUUACCAUCAGGCAAUCCAUGGUGUAGGGAAACUUUACUUAUGUAAUGAUUGUCACAAAGUCUUCAGUUACACUACAACCAUUGCGAAUCAUUGGAGAAUCCAUAAUGAAGAGAGAUCAUACUAGUUUAAUAAAUUUGGCAAAUUUUUCAGACAUUGUUCAUAACUUGCAGUUCAUCGGCGAACUCGUACUGGAGAGAAACCUUACAAAUGUCAUGAUUGUGACAAGGUCUCAGUCAAGCUUCAUUCUAUGCAAAACAUAGGAGAAUUCAUACAGGAGAGAAACCUCACAAGUGUGAUGAUUGCGGCAAAGCCUUUAAUUCACAUUCACACCUCACUAGACAUCAGAGAAUGCAUACUGGACAGAAAUCUUAUAAAUGUCAUCAGUGUGCCAAAGUCUUCAGUCUGAGCUCACUCCUUGCAGGAUAUCAGAAAAUUCAUUUUGGAGAUAGUUGUUCCAAAUACAAUGUGUAUAGCAAACCAUCAAGCAUUAAUUGACACUAGAGUCAGUUCAGCAUUGACUUGAGUUUGACUUAACAUUGAGUUGAAGCCUUAAUUGACAUUAAAGUGUUUAUGUUAAGAGGACUGGGCCAGGCACAGUGGCUCACACCUGUAAUCUGAGCGCUUUGGGAGGCCAGCACCGGUAGAUCACUUGAGUUCAGGAGUUUGAGGUCAGCCUGGCCAACAGACGUGAGCCAUUUUCCCAGCCUGUUUUUUGUUUCUUUAACAAAAACUGAUAGGGAUUUUUUUUUUUUUUUUUGAGAUGGAGUUUCACUCUUGUUGCCCAGGCUGGACUGCAAUGGAGCGAUCCCAGCUCACUACAACCUCCGCCUCCCAGGUUCAAGCAAUUCUCCUGCCUCAGCCUCCAGAGUAGCUAGGAUUACAGGCAUGAGCCACCACGCCCAGCUAAUUUUGUAUUUUUAGUAGAGAUGGGGUUUCUCCAUGUUGGUUAGGCUGGUCUUGAACUCCCAGCCUCAGAUGAUCCACCCACCUCGGCCUCCCAAAGUGCUGGGAUUACAGGCGUGAGCCACUGCGCCCAGCCCCAGUGAUAAGGAUUUUUAUGGGUACCGUGUUGAAUCUAAAUCACAUUGGGUUAUAUAAUCAUUUAACAAUAUUAAUUUUUCCAAACCAUAAGUAUGGGUUGUAGCUCUAUGUUUCUAAUCAUUUUGAUCAAUGUUUGUAGAUUUCAAGGUAAAAACCUCUGACCUUUUUACGUUUAUUUCUAAGUAUUUCUUACUUUAAGUUCUCCAGCCAAUGGAAGUGUUUUAAAAUUUUCUUUUAAAGUUGUUUGUUGUUAAAAGUAUGGAAAUUCAACUAAUUUUUGGUGCUGAUACUGUAUUGUGCAAAUCCACUGAAUAUGUUACUUAGUUCCAGUAGUAUUUUGGUUGACUCUUUGUGAUUUUCUGCACAGAAGAUCAUGUCGUCUACAAACAAAUAUAAUUUUACUUCUUUCUUUCUGA